AAGCGUGUGUUCAUACCACUGUACUGUAGUGUCUACUGCCUACCAUUGUGGUUUCACAGCUGUUCAUCUCAGUGCUGUUUGCCUCAAGUUCUUCAAGCUCUUCACUUGCUGUCUUCUGCUUCUCCUCCCCUCUUCUAGGCUAGCUCGCACUGGAGUCGCUGUGUUUCUCCUUUUGUGUUCUCCAUCAGCACUCUCUACUUACCUUGCUAAAUGCCUUUUCUUUCAACGCCACCUUACCCUGCCCACCCCAUGGCUGCUACCUGUUUAUUUUGUCAUUUUGCUAAGACUGUUGAAUAUUUUUAAGCACAGUAUAAGAGGCUUUAAAUUAGGGAAUGUGUCUGCCAGACAAAUAAGUGUUUCUAAUAUUUGGAGCUGCUUUUUGGAUUUUAUAAUCAACCCAUAUGGAUAGCCUUAGUUCUGGGGCUGUGACUCUGAAAGGGGCUGAUGUGACUCAGGAGUGAGCUGGUGUCAUGAGUGGAGUCUUUUGGAUACUUGCAGCUCUGAAGGUGGCAUCAGCUUUAGACCUCCUAGCAUCGAUGUUGAUGUGAUGUGGUGUAAAUGUGAGAUGAUGCUGUGCUAUCUGGGGUUUCUUGCAGUGCCUUGUUACCCAAUGCAUAAGUCUCUGAAAACUCCAUAAGUGUCCAUCACUACUUACCACAGAAACUGAAGGAAGCCUGAUCUUGGGAUGACCUUGUUGCAUUAAGAGAAAAAGGAAAUGAAGUUUGCCAUCUGUAUGUAAACCCGCUAUUUGUAUCAUCAACAUGCAGUGUCGAGAAAGUCACCAUAGAAUUGUUUUGCCUAAAGUUUAUUUUACUCACUUUUAGGAACAAAGCUGUUAUGUAAAGCCUUAGUUGUUUGUAAUGUUCUGCAUUUUGGGGCAGAAGUCCCAAAUGUACUUCAAGUUUUCUGUCCAUGGAUUGGGAAAUAGAAGUCAUGUAUGAAAGGAGAGGAGAUAGCAGACAGUCUUUGAGAUGAACUAUUUCAAGGACCAGUCUGCAGUUCUUCCAAGUUAGAGUUCUGAAUAUGUGGUUAGGCUAGUGAUGAUGAUAGAACACCCCAGUUCUGACUGCAUCAUUGCCCAGACAGACCCAGUAUCUUUCACCAUUUUAUUCCUGACCAAACAACGUUCAUUUCCCAGUAUCUUAGUCUCUCCUAAAGGAAAAAGAACUACGGUAGCUGGCAUCCAUAGAGUACUGUGAUGUACCACUCUUGGUAAAACGGAAAUGUCUGAUUGGAGUGUGUUUCAAGCCAGGCUUUUCUAUAAUUCGCUUGUUCCACUUUUCACUCCUGAGUUUUUGAGGUUUUAAUCUUGAGACUUUUUCUCUGCAGUGCCUCAGUUACUACUAUGGAAUAACAUAAUAAGCGAAGAGGAUGACUUCUCUGCUGGGCUGUGGUUCUUCUAGUAAUUCCGCUACUCCUGGGUCAUUGCCUGGGGUGAGGAGGCCAGGUUAUCUUCUGGAGGCUCACCACACCUUGGUGUCCAGAUGUGCCCUAGGACUGCAGUGGAGAGAACGCAUUCCCUGGGAUGAAAAACCCUGCUCAAGCCUGGGUACAGUGACCCAAGGUGACAGCAAUGACAGUGGCCCUUCAGAAAGGAGCAAGUGGAGGUGGACCCUGCCUCAAACAGAACUCCAUCCGGCACAACCUGUCACUGCAUAGUCGAUUCAUGCGGGUCCAGAAUGAGGGAACUGGCAAGAGCUCUUGGUGGAUCAUCAACCCUGAUGGGGGGAAGAGCGGAAAAGCCCCCCGGCGGCGGGCUGUCUCCAUGGACAAUAGCAACAAGUAUACCAAGAGCCGUGGCCGCGCAGCCAAGAAGAAGGCAGCCCUGCAGACAGCCCCCGAAUCAGCUGACGACAGUCCCUCCCAGCUCUCCAAGUGGCCUGGCAGCCCCACGUCACGCAGCAGUGAUGAGCUGGAUGCGUGGACGGACUUCCGUUCACGCACCAAUUCUAACGCCAGCACAGUCAGUGGCCGCCUGUCGCCCAUCAUGGCAAGCACAGAGUUGGAUGAAGUCCAGGACGAUGAUGCGCCUCUCUCGCCCAUGCUCUACAGCAGCUCAGCCAGCCUGUCACCUUCAGUAAGCAAGCCGUGCACGGUGGAACUGCCACGGCUGACUGAUAUGGCAGGCACCAUGAAUCUGAAUGAUGGGCUGACUGAAAACCUCAUGGACGACCUGCUGGAUAACAUCACGCUCCCGCCAUCCCAGCCAUCGCCCACUGGGGGACUCAUGCAGCGGAGCUCUAGCUUCCCGUAUACCACCAAGGGCUCGGGCCUGGGCUCCCCAACCAGCUCCUUUAACAGCACGGUGUUCGGACCUUCAUCUCUGAACUCCCUACGCCAGUCUCCCAUGCAGACCAUCCAAGAGAACAAGCCAGCUACCUUCUCUUCCAUGUCACACUAUGGUAACCAGACACUCCAGGACCUGCUCACUUCGGACUCACUUAGCCACAGCGAUGUCAUGAUGACACAGUCGGACCCCUUGAUGUCUCAGGCCAGCACCGCUGUGUCUGCCCAGAAUUCCCGCCGGAACGUGAUGCUUCGCAAUGAUCCGAUGAUGUCCUUUGCUGCCCAGCCUAACCAGGGAAGUUUGGUCAAUCAGAACUUGCUCCACCACCAGCACCAAACCCAGGGCGCUCUUGGUGGCAGCCGUGCCUUGUCGAAUUCUGUCAGCAACAUGGGCUUGAGUGAGUCCAGCAGCCUUGGGUCAGCCAAACACCAGCAGCAGUCUCCUGUCAGCCAGUCUAUGCAAACCCUCUCGGACUCUCUCUCAGGCUCCUCCUUGUACUCAACUAGUGCAAACCUGCCCGUCAUGGGCCAUGAGAAGUUCCCCAGCGACUUGGACCUGGACAUGUUCAAUGGGAGCUUGGAAUGUGACAUGGAGUCCAUUAUCCGUAGUGAACUCAUGGAUGCUGAUGGGUUGGAUUUUAACUUUGAUUCCCUCAUCUCCACACAGAAUGUUGUUGGUUUGAACGUGGGGAACUUCACUGGUGCUAAGCAGGCCUCAUCUCAGAGCUGGGUGCCAGGCUGAAGGAUCACUGAGGAAGGGGAAGUGGGCAAAGCAGACCCUCAAACUGACACAAGACCUACAGAGAAAACCCUUUGCCAAAUCUGCUCUCAGCAAGUGGACAGUGAUACCGUUUACAGCUUAACACCUUUGUGAAUCCCACGCCAUUUUCCUAACCCAGCAGAGACUGUUAAUGGCCCCUUACCCUGGGUGAAGCACUUACCCUUGGAACAGAACUCUAAAAAGUAUGCAAAAUCUUCCUUGUACAGGGUGGUGAGCCGCCUGCCAGUGGAGGACAGCACCCCUCAGCACCACCCACCCUCAUUCAGAGCACACCGUGAGCCCCCGUCGGCCAUUCUGUGGUGUUUUAAUAUUGCGAUGGUUUAUGGGACGUUUUAAGUGUUGUUCUUGUGUUUGUUUUCCUUUGACUUUCUGAGUUUUUCACAUGCAUUAACUUGCGGUAUUUUUCUGUUAAAAUGUUAACCGUCCUUCCCCUAGCAAAUUUAAAAACAGAAAGAAAAUGUUGUACCAGUUACCAUUCCGGGUUCGAGCAUCACAAGCUUUUGAGCGCAUGGAACUCCAUAAACUAACAAAUUACAUAAACUAAAGGGGGAUUUUCUUUCUUCUUUUGUUUGGUAGAAAAUUAUCCUUUUCUAAAAACUGAACAAUGGCACAAUUGUUUGCUAUGUGCACCCGUCCAGGACAGAACCGUGCAUAGGCAAAAGGAGUGGAGCACAGCGUCCGGCCCAGUGUGUUUCCGGUUCUGAGUCAGGGUGAUCUGUGGACGGGACCCCAGCACCAAGUCUACGGGUGCCAGAUCAGUAGGGCCUGUGAUUUCCUGUCAGUGUCCUCAGCUAAUGUGAACAGUGUUGGUCUGCUGGUUAGAAACUAGAAUAUUGAUAUUUUCAGGAAAGAAAUCAGCUCAGCUCUCCACUCAUUGCCAAAUGUCACUAAAGGGUUUAGUUUUAAGGAGAAAGAAAAGGAAAAAAAAAAAAAACAAAAAAGUCCUGUUUUGCUUUGCAGAACAAAUGAACUUACAGGUGAGCAUUAAGCUUGCAGUGAGAAAUGUGCGAAGAGUAAAAACCCAAGUCAAUGCUGAGGCAGUUCUAACUUCACUGUUUUCCUAAAUACACAUCCUUGAUUAUUUUCAGCCUUGCUAUAUAAUCUGAUCUGCUAGAAGUGUAUGAGUGAGAGGCAAUAGCAUACAAACUGAUUUUUUAAAUAUAAGCUUAGGUUGUAAUUGUACAAGUGACUCAAUGGAAGUACAAAAUAGGGCAGUUUUAACUUUUUUUUCUGCUUCUAUGGAUUUCAUUUUGUUGUGUUUUCAAAAAGUUAUGGUGCUGUAUAGGUGCUUUCUGUUUAACCUGGAAAGUGUGAUUAUAUUCGUUACCUUCUUUGGUAGACGGAAUAGUUGGGACCACCUUUGGUACAUAAGAAAUUGGUAUAACGAUGCUCUGAUUAGCACAGUAUAUGCAUACUUCUCCAAAGUGAUAUAUGAAGACUCUUUUCUUUGCAUAAAAAGCAUUAGGCAUAUAAAUGUAUAAAUAUAUUUUAUCAUGUACAGUACAAAAAUGGAACCUUAUGCAUGGGCCUUAGGAAUACAGGCUAGUAUUUCAGCACAGACUUCCCUGCUUGAGUUCUUGCUGAUGCUUGCACCGUGACAGUGGGCACCAACACAGACGUGCCACCCAACCCCCUGCACACACCACCGGCCACCAGGGGCCCCCUUGUGCGCCUUGGCUUUAUAACUCCUCUGGGGGUGAUAUUGGUGGUGAUCACAGCUCCUAGCAUAAUGAGAGUUCCAUUUGGUAUUGUCACACGUCUCCUGCCUCGCUUGGGUUGCCAUGUUUGAGCGAUGGCCCUGUUGAUUUCACCCUGCCUUUUACUGAAUCUGUAAAUUGUUGUGCAAUUGUGGUUAUAGUAGACUGUAGCACAUUGCCUUUUCUAAACUGCUACAUGUUUAUAAUCUUCAUUUUUAAAGUAUGUGUAAUUUUUUUAAGUAUGUAUUCUAUUCAUAUGGUCUGCUUGUCAGUGAGCCAGACUUGCUUACUAUAUUCCUUUAUAAUAAUGCUAGCCACUUCCUGGAUUCUUUAGUAAUGUGCUGUAUGCAAGAACUUUCCAGUAGCAGUGAAGGAGGGUUGCCUCUCCAAGCUUCCUAAGGGAUGCUGCCCUGUGUGGGGAUGCAUUGCAGAGGCACUAGUAGCAUGGGGGCUAGAGUGGGGAGCGAGAUGUAAAAGGGUGGGGGGAUAGGAGAAUUCCAGAGUGCUUCCAGCAUUAGGGUCCUGAGAACUUCUGAGUUCAGAGAAACAUGCAAAGUGACUAACAAAAUAGCUACUUACCUUUGCAGUUUUACAGACCCUGGGAGCUGCUUUGGGAGUGAGAAAGGCAACCCUCCAAUGUGUUUCAACUUUAAAAUGUUGAAUUCUUUUCAGACAUGGUAUCUCAUUUAUUCUCCUUUUCUAGCGUUUGUUGAAUUUCAGGCAGAAUGUCUUACAGAAUGUCCUAGAACCAGAUUAUCAUUUAAUCUGAAACAGCUGAGGAAGGGACAGAGAAGGUACAAGGGCAAGGCAGCACAAAACAGAUCAGGAGAAUGAAGAGGGAAUGCUUUGGUUUUUUGUUUUGUUUUGUUUUUUCUUUUUCAAGUAACUAAAACAGCAUCUACAUGUAGAGUGUUGUGGAGAGCUGAGACCAGGGUAAAGUCAAGUGCAGCAUCAGUACUGCGAGACCCACCAGCCCCUGGAGAGGGUCAGCCGAGAAUCUGGUAGUGAAGCCUGUCUAGGGUCCCGGCACCCUCACCCUCAGCCACCUGCAGAGAGGCCAGGGCCCCAGAGACUAGCCUGGUUCUGAAGUGGGCAGGGGUGCUGCCAGAGCCCUCUGCCCCUUAUGUUGAGACCCUGCUUUCAGGACAGGCCAGCCGUUGGCCACCAUGUCACAUUCUGAGUGAGUGUCACAGGUCCCUAACAAUAAUUUUCUGAUCUGGAGCAUAUCAGCAGAAUGCUUAGCCUCAAGGGGCCUGGCAGCUGUAAUGUUUGAUUUAUGAUGAGAACUAUCCGAGGCCACCCUUGGCCUCUAAAUAAGCUGCUCUAGGGAGCCGCCUACUUUUUGAUGAGAAAUUAGAAGAGUACCUAAUGUUGAAAACAUGACAUGCGCUCUUGGGAUCUGCUGUUCUCUCCAGGGCUCCAGAACCUGAUACCUGUUACCAAAGCUAGGAAAGAGCUUUAUCACAAGCCUUCACUGUCCUGGCAUGAGAACUGGCUGCCAGGCUCAGUGUACCCCAUUAACUGUGAAUGAAUCUGAGCUUGGUUUCCUUUAUUGCUUCCUCUGCAAUAUGAUUGCUGAAACACAUUUUAAAAAUUCAGAAGCUUGUCACUCCUGUUAAUGGGAGGAUCAGUCACACAUGUGUAGUACAAGGCGGACUUUGUGUUUGUUUUUGGUGUUAAUUUUUAGCAUUGUGUGUGUUGCUUCCCCACCCUGAGGAGAGGACACCAUGGCUUACUACUCAGGACAAGUAUGCCCCGCUCAGGGUGUGAUUUCAGGUGGCUUCCAAACUUGUACGCAGUUUAAAGAUGGUGGGGACAGACUUUGCCUCUACCUAGUGAACCCCACUUAAAGAAUAAGGAGCAUUUGAAUCUCUUGGAAAAGGCCAUGAAGAAUAAAGCAGUCAAAAAGAAGUCCUCCAUGUUGGUGCCAAGGACUUGCGAGGGGAAAUAAAAAUGUUAUCCAGCCUGACCAACAUGGAGAAACCCCGUCUCCAUUAAAAAUACAAAAUUAGCCUGGCAUGGUGGCGCAUGCCUGUAAUCCCAGCUACUCUGGAGGCUGAGGCAGGAGAAUCGCUUGAACCCAGGAGGCGGAGGUCGCAGUGAGCCGAGAUCAUGCCAGUGCACUCCAGCCUGGGUAACAAGAGUGAAACUCCGUGUCAAAAAAAAAAAAAAAAUGUUACUCAUCCUCUCUGAAAGCAAAAAGGAAACCCUAACAGCUCUGAACUCUGGUUUUAUUUUUCUUGCUGUAUUUGGGUGAACAUUGUAUGAUUAGGCAUAAUGUUAAAAAAAAAAAUUUUUUUUUGGUAGAAAUGCAAUCACCAGUAAAGAGGUACGAAAAAGCUAGCCUCUCUCAGAGACCGGGGAGGCAGAGUACUACUAGAGGAAGUGAAGUUCUGAUGGAAUCAUGCCUGUCAAAUGAGGUCUUGAAGCGGAUGCCCAAAUAAAAGAGUAUAUUUUAUCUAAAUCUUAAGUGGGUAACAUUUUAUGCAGUUUAAAUGAAUGGAAUAUUUUCCUCUUGUUUAGUUGUAUCUGUUUGUAUUUUUCUUUGAUGAAUGAUUGGUCAUGAGGCCUCUUGCCACACUCCAGAAAUACGUGUGCGGCUGCUUUUAAGAACUAUGUGUCUGGUCACUUAUUUCUCUAAAAUUAUCUCAUUGCCUGGCAAUCAGUCUUCUCUUGUAUACUUGUCCUAGCACAUUAUGUACAUGGGAAAUGUAAACAAAUGUGAAGGAGGACCAGAAAAAUUAGUUAAUAUUUAAAAAAAUGUAUUGUGCAUUUUGGCUUCACAUGUUUAACUUUUUUUAAGAAAAAAGUUGCAUGAAUGGAAAAAAAAAUCUGUAUACAGUAUCUGUAAAAACUAUCUUAUCUGUUUCAAUUCCUUGCUCAUAUCCCAUAUAAUCUAGAACUAAAUAUGGUGUGUGGCCAUAUUUAAACACCUGAGAGUCAAGCAGUUGAGACUUUGAUUUGAAGCACCUCAUCCUUCUUUCAAUGCGAACACUAUCAUAUGGCAUUCUUACUGAGGAUUUUGUCUAACCAUAUGUUGCCAUGAAUUAACUCUGCCGCCUUUCUUAAGGAUCAAAACCAGUUUGAUUUGGGAAUCUUCCCCUUUCCAAAUGAAAUAGAGAUGCAGUACUUAACUUUCCUUGGUGUUUGUAGAUAUUGCCUUGUGUAUUCCACUUAAAACCGUAAUCUAGUUUGUAAAAGAGAUGGUGACGCAUGUAAAUAAAGCAUCAGUGACACUCUAUCUUA